AGAGCCUAGGCCCUUCCUCGCUUUUCCAAGUCUUUUGCCAACCAGUUUGUUAGACUUUCCCCUAUUCUGAAUCAGGUGGGAGCACAGCAUGGCCGUGGGAACGAGUGCUCUCAGCAAGGAGCCGUGGUGGACCCUGCCCGAAAACUUUCAUUCUCCAAUGGUGUUCCACAUGGAAGAGGACCAGGAGGAGCUCAUCUUCGGACUUGAUGACACGUACCUUCGCUGCAUUGAGCUGCACAGCCACACCCUUAUUCAGCUGGAGAGGUGUUUCACAGCUACAGGCCAGACACGUGUGACUGUAGUCGGACCACCAAUGGCAAAGCAGUGGCUGCUGCUCAUGUUCCAUUGCGUGGGGAGCCAGGACUCCAAGUGUCACGCUCGAGGUCUGAAGAUGCUAGAGCGUGUCCGAAGCCAGCCCCUGACCAAUGAUGACCUGGUCACCUCCGUUAGCCUGCCACCGUACACCGGAGACUGAUCUCCCCUGGGAAGAGGGGAUGAGAGGAGAAGUCUUGGCUUCGCUUUUGGUGAGAAAGACAUGAAAAACACUGAAGAAAGUUUGAAUUUGUGGCCAGACCUGCCCCUCUCAGGCCUUCUAGGCAUGUGUCUGAGGGAAGUCUCCUGAGUGUUAGAAGUGUUAUUGGCAAAGCAAUCCAAUAAAAUAAGCUACCUAUGAUGCAAA